ACUUCACGUGACCGCGCGGCGGCCGCUGCGGCGCGAUGGCGGCGGGGCUGGCGCGGCUCCUGUUGCUCCUCGGGCUCUCGGCCGGCGGGCCCGCGCCGGCAGGUGCAGCGAAGAUGAAGGUGGUGGAGGAGCCCAACGCGUUUGGGGUGAACAACCCGUUCUUGCCUCAGGCCAGUCGCCUCCAGGCCAAGAGGGAUCCUUCACCCGUGUCUGGACCCGUGCAUCUCUUCCGACUCUCGGGCAAGUGCUUCAGCCUGGUGGAGUCCACGUACAAGUAUGAGUUCUGCCCGUUCCACAACGUGACCCAGCACGAGCAGACCUUCCGCUGGAACGCCUACAGUGGGAUCCUCGGCAUCUGGCACGAGUGGGAGAUCGCCAACAACACCUUCACGGGCAUGUGGAUGAGGGACGGUGACGCCUGCCGUUCCCGGAGCCGGCAGAGCAAGGUGGAGCUGGCGUGUGGAAAAAGCAACCGGCUGGCCCAUGUGUCCGAGCCGAGCACCUGCGUCUACGCGCUGACGUUCGAGACCCCCCUCGUCUGCCACCCCCACGCCUUGCUAGUGUACCCAACCCUGCCAGAGGCCCUGCAGCGGCAGUGGGACCAGGUAGAGCAGGACCUGGCCGAUGAGCUGAUCACCCCCCAGGGCCAUGAGAAGUUGCUGAGGACACUUUUUGAGGAUGCUGGCUACUUAAAGACCCCAGAAGAAAAUGAACCCACCCAGCUGGAGGGAGGUCCUGACAGCUUGGGGUUUGAGACCCUGGAAAACUGCAGGAAGGCUCAUAAAGAACUCUCAAAGGAGAUCAAAAGGCUGAAAGGUUUGCUCACCCAGCACGGCAUCCCCUACACGAGGCCCACAGAAACUUCCAACUUGGAGCACUUGGGCCACGAGACGCCCAGAGCCAAGUCUCCAGAGCAGCUGCGGGGUGACCCAGGACUGCGUGGGAGUUUGUGACCUUGUGGUGGGAGAGCAGAGGUGGACGCGGCCGAGAGCCCUACAGAGAAGCUGGCUGGUAGGACCCGCAGGGACCAGCUGACCAGGCUUGUGCUCAGAGAAGCAGACAAAACAAAGAUUCAAGGUUUUAAUUAAUUCCCAUACUGAUAAAAAUAACUCCAUGAAUUCUGUAAACCAUUGCAUAAAUGCUAUAGUGUAAAAAAAUUUAAACAAGUGUUAACUUUAAACAGUUCGCUACAAGUAAAUGAUUAUAAAUACUACCUUCUGGGUUAAGAAAAUUCCAUUCAAAUAACAUUCUCAUGUAAAUACUCAAACAUACAGAUUGAGGCUUCCAGAAAUUAAUCCACUUGAGGCGUCCACGCGGAACAAGGUCUGCUGACCACAGUUACACACGUCGUGACACCACUGUAUCACGGCGAAUGUCGAACACUAGAGUUACAGACGACAGGCAACAAGAACAUGCAGAGCCGGCCGCCAGCCAGCUCCUACGCCCCGUGCCCGCCAUGGCCACAGGGGGGAGCUGCUGGGCGCGCCUCCACCUCAGCCUCCACGGGGCACCUUCCAGCCACUGCUGUGCCUCAGCCACCUAGGAGCCAUCCCUGAGGCCAUGGCCACCAAGACAGGUGAGGGAGGCCCCAGGGCACACAGCCCCAGGAUCUUGCCCCCAUUUCCAACCCUGGCAGCGCUGCCAGCCAUUCUUUGGUCUUCCCACUGCUCACCUGUCCUCAGAGCCAGUACUGAUCUAGGGGAGCAGGUGCCACCUCCAUCUCCCAGCUGUCCCCCCACCCCUGGGGCUCCCCAGCUCUACCACCCCGGAAGCUGAGCCCUGGAGACACCCUGAGGGGCGGGCGCCACCUCCUUCCCAGAAAGAGCAGAGCAGCUGGCAGACUAGAGCUCAGCUGCUCCUGACCACUGACAACCGGGAGAUGUCUCGGCAGACACCACUUAUCCCAGAAAAGACCAGAGGCUCCAAAUGGGAACCAAGUGCAUAAAUACAAAUAAAAACAGAGUUUACACAUCGA